GGGAGAGCGCGGAGCCAGCGGAGCGCGGAGGCCCCAGCGCCAGCACCCGCGCGGGCGGUGAGCGUGAGUGUGGCGCAGGGUCGCCCCUCCCCAGCCUGGCCCCGGCAGUGCGGGCCCCGGGAGCGCCCUGACGGCUAGUCCUCGUGCAGCUUAGUGGCGCAGUGGCGGCAGCAGCAUGAGCACCCCCCGGCCUGCUCCACCACAGCCAGGCGCUGCUGAGGGGGCUGGAGGCCCAGAAGGGAAGGCUGUGGCAGGUGCCUGGGAGAAGGGCCCUCGGCUGGGCCAGCGGCUGCCCUCAAUCGUGGUGGAGCCCAGCGAGGCGGACCCUGUGGAAAGUGGGGAGCUGCGCUGGCCCCUGGAGAGUGCCCAGAGGGGCCCCUCUCAGAGCCGGGCUGCUGCUGCCCCCUCGCCGAGUCUGCCCGGAGAACCAGGGAAAGCUGCAGAUAACGCUGGCAGCGAGUGUGCCUGCUCCGAGGACCCAGCAGCCCCGGCCCGGGGAUAGGACAAGGACGUGGCUGGGCUCUGCUGUCUGACUGCUGAGGGCCUCUGCCCCAGGGUGGCCGGGCUGAUGCACAGGAGGGCCGGGCCUGCCCAGCCUGGAAAGCCCAGAGGCUGCUUCCUGUGUCACAGGGUCUGGACCGCAGCCCUGCCCUCUUCUGCCCAUGGCCCAGGUCUGGAUCACACCCCGCUUUGUUCCGUGGUUUGAAGCAGAAAUAAAGGCACUUCCUGGUG